AGAGGUGUUCGAAGCCGGGUGGUGCGUGGGCUACCCCAACCUGUGUGGCUGGGCCGCGGUCUCCCCUCAAGGGCCUGGGGCCGUGCCUCGGGUGUACGCGUAGGGGUCUGUGUGCUGGGGGUGGCUCACCGGGCAGCGUGGGUGAGCGGCGCAGCGGCGGCAGCGGAGAGCGAGAGAGGGGAGCAGGCUUCUAACCCUCCUUUAUGUGACUCAGAGAAAGGAGACCUCAUUCCAAGUUCCAGGAUUAAUUCUGAUGAAAGUAUUCUGUCUCAUGCAUCUAAUACUUUACUUGUGAAUGAAGAUUCAUUAUGAGGUGCUAUACGUGGAUGACCUGCUUAGUUUUAAUUUUUGGAGAAAUACAUUUUAUAAAACAUUUUCAUCAGAUUGCUAAAAUUGUGAGUAAUGGUAAUGAUACCAUGAUUAUAUUCUGGUUAAUUUAAUACCUUUCCUUUUUACAAUAUGUUUCUGUCUAAAUAUAUAUUUUUUAGUGUCAUUACCUACUGAGUUUCUGUGAAAAGAAUUUCCUUUGCCUGUUAAAACAAUCGUUGAAAUUAAUGUUUUUACUGUUUUUUUCUUUGACAAUUUUUUGAAUUUUCUUUUUGAAGGUGUUAGCACUAGUUUCCAGAAGGUAAAGCACAGAUAUAGAUGACUACUUAAAGCAAAUGACCUUAGAAAAUGCCCUUAAGAUUAAUGUUUAACAUAUAGUUUAAUAUGUAUAGCUAUUUUUAUUUUAGAAGUGGGAAAGGAUUGUUUUCCUGUAAUGAAGUCCAUCUUGUAUUACUGAGUCAAGGAAACUAUAAUCAACAUUUGGGUGCCACUUGAAGAAUGGAUGAUGAUGAUUUUGGUGGUUUUGAGGCUGCGGAGACUUUUGAUGGUGGAAGUGGUGAAACCCAAACAACAUCUCCUGCUAUUCCUUGGGCUGCCUUUCCUGCAGUAUCUGGAGUCCAUCUUUCACCAUCUUCUCCUGAGAUUGUACUGGACCGUGACCACUCUUCUUCCAUUGGCUGCCUCUCUUCUGAUGCCAUUAUUUCAUCACCAGAGAAUACACAUGCAGCAAAUAGCAUUAUUCAGCAAUCAACACACACUCAUCUGGAUAUCUCACUUUUUCCAUUGGGUUUAACUGAUGAAAAAAGUAAUGGAACAAUUGCCCUUGUGGAUGAUUCUGAGGAUCCUGGAGCCAAUGUAUCUAACAUACAGCUUCAGCAAAAAAUUUCAAGUCUGGAGAUUAAACUCAAAGUAUCUGAAGAAGAAAAACAGAGAAUUAAACAGGAUGUGGAAUCAUUGAUGGAAAAGCAUAAUGUCUUAGAAAAAGGCUUUCUAAAAGAAAAAGAGCAAGAGGCCAUUUCUUUUCAAGAUAGAUACAAAGAACUUCAGGAAAAACAUAAACAAGAAUUGGAAGACAUGAGGAAAGCUGGUCACGAAGCCCUCAGCAUUAUUGUGGAUGAAUAUAAGGCACUACUGCAGUCUUCAGUUAAGCAACAAGUAGAAGCUAUUGAAAAACAGUACAUUUCUGCAAUUGAGAAACAGGCACACAAGUGUGAGGAGUUGCUAAAUGCUCAGCAUCAGAGGCUCCUUGAAAUGCUAGAUACAGAGAAGGAACUGUUAAAAGAAAAAAUAAAGGAAGCUUUGAUUCAGCAAUCUCAAGAACAGAAGGAAAUAUUGGAAAAGUGUUUGGAGGAAGAAAGGCAAAGAAAUAAAGAGGCAUUAGUAUCCGCUGCAAAGCUUGAAAAAGAAGCAGUGAAGGAUGCAGUUUUAAAAGUCGUAGAAGAAGAAAGAAAAAAUUUAGAAAAAGCGCAUGCUGAAGAAAGGGAAUUAUGGAAGACAGAACAUGCAAAAGAUCAAGAAAAAGUAUCUCAGGAAAUUCAAAAAGCUAUACAAGAACAAAGAAAAAUAAGUCAGGAAACUGUUAAGGCAGCAAUAAUAGAAGAGCAGAAACGAAGUGAAAAGGCUGUGGAAGAGGCAGUGAAAAGAACAAGAGAUGAAUUGAUAGAGUAUAUAAAAGAACAGAAAAGGCUCGAUCAAGUCAUCCGCCAAAGAAGCCUGUCCAGUUUGGAACUGUUCCUCUCCUGUGCACAGAAACAGUUAAGUGCUUUAAUAGCUACGGAACCAGUUGACAUUGAAUAAAAAGAACAUGACAAACCCACACUGGCAUUGGAUAAAUCAUAUUACACCUUCAAAAUACACACUCUGAAUUAUAAAGAUGUGUUUGUUUUCUUUCCAAAUCAUGUAGAAUUGAUUUCCAGUUCAAGGAUAAACCAAAACAAUAUUUAGAACUAUCAAGUGAUCUAAUUUAUUUUCUUUUGGUUUCUUCUUUACAUUUACUGUUAUUUUAUUAUUAUUAGUAGUAGCAGCAACAGAGUAUGAUAUGACCCAAAAGCCAUUGUAAAGUGCCACAUUACCAAAAUUAAUUAAGUAAACUUUAUAGCCUGUGGGAGUCUAUUAUAUAUUAUUUUGCAAAAGUAGUAAAUAUAUUAUUGUUUCAUGAUGACUCUUGAUGAGAUGCUAGAAUGUAACCAUACAUUUAUCUUAUUUUGAGGAUAGAAAUAGCAUGGAUUUCAACAUCACUUAUUUAUCUGUAUAAUUGGAAAUAAAACACCGAUAUGAUAGAGAAUCAUUCCGGCAUUACCUAACCUCUUCUGCAGUUGGAUCUAUGUAUUUUCAUUGGUCUACUGAAAACAAACAAUACAAUUAAAAGCACUAAAGAUUAUUAUAUUAAUUCAACUUUGAUCUGAUAUAUCACUUAAACUAAAGGGGUGUGUGUGGUGUAUGCUUGUUUCCUAUUUCUGCUCUUUAAAGAUACUUUGAAUCAAUAAAACCAUUAGUCUACAAAUCAAAUUGUGAACUUAAUCUCUAGAAAGAGAAUAUAACUCAGCCAUUUAUAGGAAUUUAGGUUCAAGUACAGGAUAUAUGAAAUCUUUUCCCAGUAUUUCAGAAUGUACUUAAUUCACAGGCAGGAUGCUUCAAUGCAAAAUCAUGAAUAUUUUUAAUUCAAAACUAAAAUGUCAUUAAUAUGUAUGUAUGCAAAUGUUUUAUCUUAUUUUCUGAAAUGCAUCUACUUUCAUGGGCUUUGUACGUUUCUGAGAUUUCUCAGUGUAAUAAAAAGAGCUCCCAAACUUA